CUGGCUUGUUCCGGCGUCCGGCCUGGCAUGCGGGUGCUGCGGCUGCUGCGGCUGCCGCCGCCGCUGCUGCCGCUGCCGCGGGGGCUGCGGCUUGGGAAGCUCCGCGCUUCCGCAGGCCUGGCCUCCGCCGCCCGGGCCCCCGCAGCCUGUCGCUGGACCCCGCGCCGGCCCAGCGCACCGCCCUCAGGCCCCGAGCCCCGCCCUGGCCUCCGCCUCGGCCUCGCCUCCAGCCCCGGGACGCGGCCCGCCACCGCCGCUGCCGCCAGCCCAGACGCGCCGCCCGCAUGCGCCGCGACCAUGGAGCGCCCCGAAGCGGGAGGAAUUAAUUCCAAUGAGUGUGAAAAUGUAUCAAGAAAAAAGAAAAUGUCAGAGGAAUUUGAAGCCAAUACUAUGGAUUCUCUGGUAGACAUGCCAUUUGCUACUGUAGAUAUUCAGGAUGACUGUGGAAUCACUGAUGAACCUCAAAUAAAUUUGAAGAGAAGUCAAGAAAAUGAAUGGGUCAAGAGUGAUCAAGUAAAGAAGAGGAAAAAAAAGAGAAAAGAUUAUCAACCCAACUAUUUCCUGUCCAUUCCAAUCACCAACAAAGAGAUUAUAAAAGGAAUUAAGAUCCUGCAGAAUGCAAUAAUACAACAAGAUGAGCGACUGGCCAAAGCAAUGGUCAGUGAUGGUUCCUUUCAUAUUACCCUGCUGGUGAUGCAAUUAUUAAAUGAAGAUGAAGUAAACAUUGGUAUUGAUGCUCUUUUGGAAUUGAAACCAUUCAUAGAAGAACUCCUCCAGGGAAAACAUUUGACUUUGCCCUUUCAAGGGAUUGGUACUUUUGGAAAUCAGGUUGGAUUUGUGAAGCUGGCAGAAGGAGAUCAUGUAAACUCACUUUUGGAGAUAGCAGAGACUGCAAAUAGGACAUUUCAAGAAAAAGGCAUCCUGGUAGGAGAGAGCAGAAGUUUUAAACCUCAUUUGACCUUCAUGAAGUUGUCAAAAUCACCGUGGCUCCGUAAGAAUCCUAGGGGGUUCCUCAUGCAAAUUCAGACAUCUGAUGGCCUGCUCUCAUAUACCAGAGUUUUGGAGAUGGGCAUGCAGAUUAAUAUCCGCUCCCUGCUCUCCAUGACCCUUUGCUGCAGUUAAGACUGAUUUGCAGCUCUAGAAAUGAAGGCCAUGUGUAGUAUGGUUUCAAACUUAAUCACAGAAUGACAAUCAGUGGUGAAGGUAAUAUCUCCGUUUCAAAAUGUUUCUUUGUCUUUAUAAUAUUAACUUUGAAAUGAGAGCACCCAAGGACAUUUAUUUAAAAAAAUGCUUAAACUAUAUAUGUCAACAUUUCAAACUGCAUUUAAAUGAUUUAUUGGCAGUUAAUUUCACAGAAUCAAUCUUACCCUAUAGAAAAGUAAUAUGAGACUUGGAAUGGUUGUGAUGUAACUGAGAUCACAGUCUUAUCAGUUACAGAGCACUGUCUCUGCACCUGAGAAACCCAUCCCAUCUCAUUCUGUCUCACAUUCUUCCCUCCCACUGGCCAGCUCCAGUUCACGCAGAGUCAUUUCUACGUGUAAGGAGCUCCCUGUUCCAAAUCAUAUUAAUUAAGUAAAUAUGUAUUGAGUGCCUACUAUGUGCCAGACACUGGGUGCUGGGCACAGAGUGGUGAUCAAAAUAGAAACAGUCACUGCUUGAAUGGUACAUAAAAUCUAAAUCAGAUUGCAUUUUAUUUAGAUUAGAAUGCUUAAUAUUUAGAAAACAAAUUAUGAUUGUUUUUUUCUUGUAAAUUUGUUUGAGUUCCUUGUAGAUUCUGCAUAUUAGCCCUUUGUCAGAUGAGUAGGUUGUGAAAAUUUUCUCCUAUUUUGUAGGUUGCCUGUUCACUCUGAUGGUAGUUUCUUUUGCUGUGCAGAAGCUCUUUAGUUUAAUUAGAUCCCAUUUGUCAAUUUUGGCUUUUGUUGCCAUUGCUUUUGGUGUUUUAGACAUGAAGUCCUUGCCCAUGCCUAUGUCCUGAAUGGUAAUGCCUAGGUUUUCUUCUAGGGCUUUUAUGGUUUUAGGUCUAAUGUUUAAGUCUUUAAUCCAUCUUGAAUUAAUUUUUGUAUAAGGUGUAAGGAAGGGAUCCAGUUUCAGCUUUCUACAUAUGGCUAGCCAGUUUUCCCAGCACCAUUUAUUAAAUAGGGAAUCGUUUCCCCAUUGCUUGUUUUUCUCAGGUUUGUCAAAGAUCAGAUAGUUGUAGAUAUGCAGCGUUAUCAACAAACAACCCUAUCAAAAAGUGGGUGAAGGACAUGAACAGGCACUUCUCAAAAGAAGACAUUUAUGCAGCCAAAAAACACAUGAAAAAAUGGUCACCAUCACUGGCCAUCAGAGAAAUGCAAAUCAAAACCACAAUGAGAUACAUCUCACACCAGUUAGAAUGGCAGUCAUUAAAAAGUCAGGAAACAACAGGUGCUGGAGAGGAUGUGGAGAAAUAGGAACACUUUUACACUGUUGGUGGGACUGUAAACUAGUUCAACCAUUGUGGAAGUCAGUGUGGCCAUUCCUCAGGGAUCUAGAACUAGAAAUACCAUUUGACCCAGCCAUCCCAUUACUGGGUAUAUACCCAAAGGACUAUAAAUCAUGCUGCUAUAAAGACACGUGCACACAUAUGUUUAUUGCGGCACUAUUCACAAUAGCAAAGACUUGGAACCAACCCAAAUGUCCAACAAUGAUAGACUGGAUUAAGAAAAUGUGGCACAUAUACACCAUGGAAUACUAUGCAGCCAUAAAAAAUGAUAAGUUCAUGUCCUUUGUAGGGACAUGGAUGAAAUUGGAAAUCAUCAUUCUCAGUAAACUAUCGCAAGGACAAAAAACCAAACACUGCAGGUUCUCACUCCUAGGUGGGAAUUGAACAAUGAGAACACGUGGACACAGGAAGGGGAACAUCACACGCUGGGGACUGUUGUGGGAUGGGGGAGGGGGGAGGGAUAGCUUUAGGAGAUAUACCUAACGCUAAAUGACGAGUUAAUGGGUGCAGCACACCAGCAUGGCACAUGUAUACAUAUGUAACUAACCUGCACAUUGUGCACAUGUACCCUAAAACUUAAAGUAUAAUAAUAAUAAAAUAAAAUAAAAUAAAGAAAACAAAUUAUGAUAUUAUCAUUUUCAGUAAGCCAAAUAAGAAUUUUUUAUUUUAAUUUAUGGAAUGAGUCUAUUCCUAUCACUAUUAUAGUGGUCAGUGUUCCUGAAAGUUUAAGGAAGUAGAUCUUAGAUAUGGGGAUUCGCAAGUCAGCCGGCGUACUGGUUGAAGCUUCAGAUUUCCACCCUCUACCCUUAGAUUUAGAGAUGGACCUAGGACCUAAGCUUUUGAUGUUCAGUAAAUGCCAUAUAUGGUUCUGAUACAGAUGAUCUGCAGAGGAAUAUACUUAAGACCUGCAGGCUUAAAUAAAUAUCCAACAGUUUCUUAUGCAGCAAAUCUACUGUAAAGGUUAAAACCAGUAUGAAAAGGUGGCAUACAUACAAGAUGAUUUCAUUUAUUUACUUUACUAUAAUUCGUGGUUUGGUAUGUAGAUUAUUUGAAAAUAUAUGGUUCCUUAGUCUCAGUCUUAACGUUUUUACAUUUCCAGCUAUCUAUUUUCUUCUCUCGGCACUAAUUUUCUUCUAGAUUUUUGUUCUGAAUCCAUCCAUUGAGCUAAUGUCACAAGCAAGUGACCAUUAAAUAAAGAUGAUCGUGGAAUGUAUUGCUGGCUUUCCAUGUUAUUUAGAUUGAUAGUGAAAUAAAAGAAGGGAGUGGCGAAAUAAUAGUUUUUUUUUAAUCCACUUGCAUGUUAGGAGAUUGGACUCAUUUCACGUAUGUUAUUCUUUAUUUAAAAAGUUACUUUAAUUAUAAAAUUAUUAGCUGAAUAUAUGCUUACUGUAAACAAUUCAAAUACUUACAGACCUAUAGAGUGAAAGGUAGAGUUACUCCCUCAUUACCAUCCUGCAACCCACUUCCUCCCAACAGAAUGUCUCUCUAGGUAAACACUGCCAGUAGAUCCUUCCAGACCUUUUCCUAUGUGCUGCAAAUAUAUAUGGACAUACAUACAUGCAUAUAGUUUCUUUAAAACAGAAAUAAAACUCUCAAUAUUAUUUUGAUUUAUCAUAAUUUAAACAUUCUUCUGUUGAUGAAUAAUUAGGUUGAUUUCUGUUUCUUUGGUACCACAAACAAUGCUGUUAUGAACUUCCUUGUUCACUUUUCUUUGGGUGGAUAUGCCAGUAUUUCAAAGAACCAAUUCUUUGAAGUGGAAUUCUAAGAGCAGAGGGUAUUAGACAUUAUAAACCUUCAGAAAUACCUCAGAUUGCCUUGUCAAGCAAUAGUGACAAUUUAUACUCCCAACCGUGGUGUAUGAGAAGAACAUUUGUUAGGAUAAACUCGUGGUAGAAAGACUAUCAGAGGUCAUAUAAAAUUGAUAUGGCCCUUUGAGCUAUGAAUUAUGCAACUGACAUUAAAAAAAUGUUAAAAAUCUCAUUUUCUUUAAGAUGUCCUAGCUGCUGAUAUUAUUCUAAAGAAAUAAUUUAAAAAGAGAAGUUCUUUAUGCAUAAAGAUGUUUACUGAAGUAUUAUCAAUAAUAGGGAAAUAAUAGAAAUAACUCCCACAACAAUAGGGAAAUGUUUAAGUCAAUUAUGGUAAAUCAUAUAAAUGAUAUAAGCAGCUACUGAAGUAGAUAUAAGGAUUCUAUAACAGCAUACAAAGUAAAUAAAAUACUAUACUCUUUAGUAUAUAAAAUCUAUCCUAUAAAAUGUAUACUGUAAUUAAAAUUGUAUAAAAUGGUUUCCUUGGGUUUGCCUUGCCAGCACCUUAAUGUGUUUCAUCGCAUUUUAGAGGUAAAAAGUGGCUUCCCACAGUUACUCUCUUAGCCCAUGAUUUUUCCGGUAGAUCAGUGAAUAGAACUGACCUUAAUGUCACUCAGAAUAUAGUAUAUCCCCCUUGACAUGCUGAGGAUUCCCAUUUUGGUUUGCUGGGGUUCUGAGGAAUGGUGGGACCUUGGUGAGUGGAGUGUAAUAAGAAGUGGUGAUGAGCAAAGUUAGGUGCCCCAUGACAAUGCAGGAGUGAGGGGCAGCCACCGGAUUCAGAAAACCUGAAGAUUUUCCAUUGUCAUGGGAGUGGUCCUUCAGUUUCUGGUAUGGAGGGGUGGUGUAUAGUGAGACUGUCUGGAAAAGAGCUAAAUGAUAUCUCCUGUUGAGAUGCUCUGUUUUAAAGACUGAAGCCAGAUGGUGUCCUCCUUAUAUUUCAAUUUGACCUGCUAGAGGGUAGUCUGGAAAUGAUUUUAUGUAUGAUACUGAUGCACUGAAAGUACUGAUGCACUAAAAGCACCUAAAGUACUGGUGCUACUGUUGUCAGGGUAGACAUGAUGAUUGUUGGUAAAAAGGGGUGUGCUGUGUAGAGGAAUGCUCUGGAUUAUUACAGGAAAUAUUAUAGGAAAAUUCUGAGAUAGUAAGAUAGCCGGUCCAUUCAUUAUUGUCUAUAGGAGGUAUAAUGCGAUAUUCUGUAGUGAUAAACCAAUUGAGAUUUUUUUUUAAUCAUCUAGUCAUUGUCAUUUAAAAAGUAACCUGAAAAGCUGUUACCCAUGUCAACUUAAAAAAUUAGAUUCAAAGUCAGAGCUAUCAUCAGUCUGUUUAUGAAGGUAAAACAUCUCAUUGACAUUAAAGAUGUGGACAGAUGGCUGGUGCAGGGGAUGAGCAUUCACCCCCUGGGAGGUCGUACAGAUCUAGUGUGAGGGUUUCCCAGUGGUGUUCAGUAUUUGGUGCAGAAGUCCCUGGGCUUCCGGGGUCCUGUCCUCUGGUAGGCACUUGUUGGCAGGUAAUUGCAUGUAGUAGUAGUAACCAAAAGCCCAGUGGGGAACUAAACAUUCAAUAUAUUGUGUUCAAAAUUUUGAAAAUACAGAAACUCUCUCUCAAAUGUCCUGAUGUGAAACUUCUUCUGUGACAGCAUGAUAUUCUGGUUCCCAAGUUAGAGAGCUGAGUUGAGGCUAAGGACAGAUUCUGUGAAACAUAAGGCUUUUCUUGGCAAUUAUGUAUCUUUCUAACACCAGGAGACAUUUAGUCAAUGUGUCAGCUUUGCAUAUUCUUAGUUUCAUGAAAUUCUAAUGGGUAUUUUGCAUAAUAAAACAUCAAAAGGAAUCAUUAUCAUUGUAUUCUGUAAUUUUUUUCAUCAAAUGAAACCUCAGAAAAUCAUAUUAAAUUACUGUCUCUGAAAUAGUAACUAAAGUUCAGGUUAUUUGUAGUUUUUUCAGAAUUUAGUUGACAUAGCUAGUCCGCUAACUUGUUCAGCCUCAUGCUUUUUGUACGGUAUCUUUUUGGACUUAUUUUUCUUACUGAAUGAACUUGGGUUUCAGUGAUUUCAAUGUUGCAAAUCUUGGUUGGUUAGAAAUAUGUGCUAACACUUGAUGGCAGAAGAAGACAAGUUUCAAAUCAAACAAACAUCUUAAUGCAGAUCUCAAAAAAUAAAUGUGAUAACAUCCUCAAAAAAUAAAUGUGAUCGCCUAAUGUAUAGAUCAGUUGUUUUUAAUCACAAAUUAUUUUCUGGGCUUCUUAGGUAUCUUCCCUGAUUUAUGACUCUUUCAAAUUACUACUGUAGCUCUUAAACUGACAAAGACAUGUUUUAUGAACAUGACACCUCUUUGCAGCAGUGUUUUACAGAGUCAGAAAAUGAGAGUACUUUAGAAUGAAAAAAAUGAACUUUGAAAAUUAUUAGCGACUUUCACUUAGACUGGUUUGUUUUGAGGGCAGAAUUCAAGAUGCAAAAAGUAAGGGCUGAAGGGUGAUCAUUGGACCUGAUGAUGAUGAUGAUGUUGAGGGGAGUGGAGAAGAGGAUAUAGGACAGUCAUUGGUAGGAAUGGAAAAGGAGAGCAUAUGGUUGAAAAUUUUGUUCUGAUGCUACCAUUAAGAGGAAAUUCCAGUUCCUGAAUUGUUUGGUGAUUGAAUAUACAGAACUAGAAUUGUAAUGGAAAGUUUCUAUACUAGGUUGGUUGAAUUCAGCCUUACUCUGCAUCCCUCCCUAACUGUGAGCCCUGAUGUCAUCUUUCUUCACUCACUACCAUUAUUUACUUCUAUCUAUCUAGCUACCUAGCUAGCUGUCUGUCUGUCUGUCUGUCCAUCCAUCCAUCUAUCUAUCUAUCUAUCUAUCUCUGCAUAUUUUUUCAGGAUUUUGUUAACUGGGCCUGGUAUAGUUUGACUGCCACUCACUUUUGGGGGUCUGCAUGACAGUGAGCUUUUAUAAACCAUGUUAAAACUCAGGAGCAUUAAGACUAUUCCUUCUUAAAGGAAUCCCUGUAGUAAUUUAAAGGAGCAUGAGCUUUCCUGUUUUAGCCCUGUUGUUUAGUCCUGGACAAAAUCACAUAACCUCUCUCGAUCUCUGUUGACUUAUCGUAAAAGAAGGACUCUUGACUCCUGUGCUAUCCUGAAAUGUCUAUAAGGUAAACAGUUUGACCAAAUUGCUUAAUUUGGCUUCACACAGUUAUAUAUAUUUUUAACCUCAUAUUGGCUUUCUUUUCUGUGUGGAAGGAGAAUGACAGAAAGAAGAAAGGUCUUCAAGUACUGAUAGGAAGAUAGGGGCAAUUUAGAUCUGAAUCUUUUCACUUGUCCUCCUAGAAGCCAGAUGGAGCAACAAGGACAAUGGGAAAAAUACUCUACACAUUUUUUUUUUUUUUUGAAAGAACUAGGAUCUCACU